AUGGAUUUUAGUUGAUGGAUGACUCACUCACUACAUUCAACUGAACUGAAUCUGCUCUAUACCAGCAAAGGGACAAAUUCAGAAAAUAAAUUGAAGAUGGCCAUGCUGUAACUUCUAAACAUGGUUUGCUUCUCAGAUUUACCUAAACUAAGAAAGGUUUGCUUUAAGAAAUAGUGCUCCCUUCAGAAUGGAAGAAUUUAUCUGCCUCUUAUUUGAUGUGGAUCAGAGCUAAGAUGGCUGACUAAAUAAACAUGGGGGACUGGAAUCUCCUUGGAGAUACUCUGGAGGAAGUUCACAUCCACUCCACCAUGAUUGGAAAGAUCUGGCUCACCAUCCUGUUCAUAUUUCGAAUGCUUGUUCUGGGUGUAGCAGCUGAAGAUGUCUGGAAUGAUGAGCAGUCUGGCUUCAUCUGCAAUACAGAACAACCAGGCUGCAGAAAUGUAUGCUACGACCAGGCCUUUCCUAUCUCCCUCAUUAGAUACUGGGUUCUGCAGGUGAUAUUUGUGUCUUCACCAUCCCUGGUCUACAUGGGCCAUGCAUUGUACCGACUGAGAGUUCUUGAGGAAGAGAGGCAAAGGAUGAAAGCUCAGUUAAGAGUAGAACUGGAGGAGGUAGAGUUUGAAAUGCCUAGGGAUCGGAGGAGAUUGGAGCAAGAGCUUUGUCAGCUGGAGAAAAGGAAACUAAAUAAAGCUCCACUCAGAGGAACCUUGCUUUGCACUUAUGUGAUACACAUUUUCACUCGCUCUGUGGUUGAAGUUGGAUUCAUGAUUGGACAGUACCUUUUAUAUGGAUUUCACUUAGAGCCGCUAUUUAAGUGCCAUGGCCACCCGUGUCCAAAUAUAAUCGACUGUUUUGUCUCAAGACCAACAGAAAAGACAAUAUUCCUAUUAUUUAUGCAAUCUAUAGCCACUAUUUCACUUUUCUUAAACAUUCUUGAAAUUUUCCACCUAGGUUUUAAAAAGAUUAAAAGAGGGCUUUGGGGAAAAUACAAGUUGAAGAAGGAACAUAAUGAAUUCCAUGCAAACAAGGCAAAACAAAAUGUAGCCAAAUACCAGAGCACAUCUGCAAAUUCACUGAAGCGACUCCCUUCUGCCCCUGAUUAUAAUCUGUUAGUGGAAAAGCAAACACACACUGCAGUGUACCCUAGUUUAAAUUCAUCUUCUGUAUUCCAGCCAAAUCCUGACAAUCAUAGUGUAAAUGAUGAGAAAUGCAUUUUGGAUGAACAGGAAACUGUACUUUCUAAUGAGAUUUCCACACUUAGUACUAGUUGUAGUCAUUUUCAACACAUCAGUUCAAACAAUAACAAAGACACUCAUAAAAUAUUUGGAAAAGAACUUAAUGGUAACCAGUUAAUGGAAAAAAGAGAAACUGAAGGCAAAGACAGCAAAAGGAACUACUACUCUAGAGGUCACCGUUCUAUUCCAGGUGUUGCUAUAGAUGGAGAGAACAACAUGAGGCAGUCACCCCAAACAGUUUUCUCCUUGCCAGCUAACUGCGAUUGGAAACCGCGGUGGCUUAGAGCUACAUGGGGUUCCUCUACAGAACAUGAAAACCGGGGGUCACCUCCUAAAGGUAACCUCAAGGGCCAGUUCAGAAAGGGCACAGUCAGAACCCUUCCUCCUUCACAAGGAGAUUCUCAAUCACUUGACAUUCCAAACACUGCUGAUUCUUUGGGAGGGCUGUCCUUUGAGCCAGGGUUGGUCAGAACCUGUAAUAAUCCUGUUUGUCCUCCAAAUCACGUAGUGUCCCUAACGAACAAUCUCAUUGGUAGGCGGGUUCCCACAGAUCUUCAGAUCUAAACAGCGGUUGGCUUUUAGACAUUAUAUAUAUUAUCAGAGAAGUAGCCUAGUGGUCGUGGGGCACAGAAAAAAUAGAUAGGGGCAGCUCUAAAGACCAGCUGUUAAGACAGACAACUGCAAACUCAUUUAAGCAAGAGAAAAACAGCUCUAAUUCGAGAUUGUGAAGCAACACUUCUAAAUUCAAAGACAUAGAGUUGUCAAAUCAGGAUUUUUUUUUUUUUAAAUGAUAUCCUUUCGAAUGUAACUGAUUUUGGGAAAAUCACAUGUUCAGAAUUGAGGCUAAAUGGUUUGAUCAGGUUUUCUCUUUGAAGAGACCACAGCCUUAGGAAAUGGUUCUUGAUCUAUACAAUUCCACCUUGGACACUGGGUUAAUUCUGUUUGCCCCUGGAACACAAUCACGUAAGUUUCCUUCUAGACUGGCAUCCUGAUGUGUCUUGAGUAUAAUCACAUGUUGCUACCUAGUAAAUAAAAUCUUAAGAAGA